CAAUGAGACAGCAUGGCCCGUACUAAGCAGACUGCCCGCAAGUCGACCGGCGGCAAGGCCCCGAGGAAGCAGCUGGCUACCAAAGCGGCCCGCAAGAGCGCGCCGGCCACGGGCGGGGUGAAGAAGCCGCACCGCUACCGGCCCGGCACCGUGGCUCUGCGGGAGAUCCGGCGCUACCAGAAGUCUACGGAGCUGCUGAUCCGCAAGCUGCCCUUCCAGCGGCUGGUACGCGAGAUCGCGCAGGACUUUAAGACGGACCUGCGCUUCCAGAGCUCGGCCGUGAUGGCGCUGCAGGAGGCCAGCGAGGCCUACCUGGUGGGGCUGUUCGAAGACACGAACCUGUGCGCCAUCCAUGCCAAGCGCGUGACCAUCAUGCCCAAGGACAUCCAGUUGGCCCGCCGCAUCCGCGGGGAGCGGGCCUAAGGCAUAUUUUUAAGUGGUCGAUCUAAAGGCUCUUUUCAGAGCCACU